CGCUCGCCACUGGCUCUCUCUGCGGCAGGUUUCCCUCCGGUUACCGUGACCAAAGGGGAAAGACGCCUGCCUCCCUGCAGGCCCCAAGAUGUGCCCCAGGGGAUGCGCUGACUGCAGCCUCCGCUCGGCUCUCCCUUGAGACUGCAAUCACAGCCCUCCGUGCACACCUUCACCACAGGCCAUUUCACCCGCGAAGCGGCCGAGUGAGGCGGUCAUCCAGCUGGCGCUGAUUUUUAUCGCCCACAGCUCCUAGGACCUGUACCAGCCAUCCAGACAGUGCUUGAGCUGCAGAAACUGAGACCAGACCUCUGGCCUGGCCCUCCCCAGGGGCCUCCUUUCGUAUAGUCACUGCUUCUGCAUCAGAUACUUUCAGCUGCAACUCCCUACUGGGUGGGGCACCCAUUUCAGGCAGAAGGUUUUGGUACCCUCCACUGACCCUACACCCAGGGCUGCUACUGCCGCUUGUGGCUUCAGGAUGAAAGGUGAGACCCCGGUGAACAGCACUAUGAGUAUUGGGCAAGCACGCAAGAUGGUGGAACAGCUUAAGAUUGAAGCCAGCUUGUGUCGGAUAAAGGUGUCCAAGGCAGCAGCAGACCUGAUGACUUACUGUGAUGCCCACGCCUGUGAGGAUCCCCUCAUCACCCCUGUGCCCACUUCGGAGAACCCCUUCCGGGAGAAGAAGUUCUUCUGUGCUCUCCUCUGAGCUCCCCUGUCCCUUCUCACAACUCCUCCCUUUUCCCUCUCCUGGGCCCUUCCUUAGGUCAGUAAUUGUUGUGAGCCCCUUAGGCUCCUUGCAUCCCAUCCCUAACCCUUGCCUGACCAUGUGAGGUUAUCUGAAGCACAAGGCCCACCCUCACCUAUCUGUCGACCCCAUUUCCUACCACCUUUGUGGCCGACCCCAAGCACCCCAGAGAUAUGAGGCACCCUUUGCUCCACCCACAGCAGGGCCCCGUCAGACUCUGCCAGCGCGUCCUGCCCGCUUCCCUCGGUGACCUGCUCAGACAAUGGAGAGGGAUGGGCCAGGUUCUUGCUCUCAGUCUCACCUGGAGCUACUGGGAGGGUAAAGCCAUUUGAAGAAUAAAGUCAUCCAGAGCCUCA